GCAGGGUGGGGACCCGGCGGCUGCUGGCCGGUAGUGACUGGUGGGCGCGCUCGAGGACUCCAAGGGGCGCAGCCCGGGGGCAGACCCUUGGGUCGGGCGGGGAUCUUACGCUUCCCUUACCCGCCCCCUUUUGUCUUUCACCUCAGCCCCGCCGGCUGCUGUGGGAGCGGCGGCCGUCCCUCUCCUGGAGGUCGUCUCCUGGCAUCCUCGGGGCCGCAGGAAGGAAGAGGAGGCAGCGGCCGGAGCCCUGGUGGGCGGCCUGAGGUGAGAGCCCGACCGGCCCCUUUGGGAAUAUGGCGACCGGUGGCUACCGGACCAGCAGCGGCCUCGGCGGCAGCACCACAGACUUCCUGGAGGAGUGGAAGGCGAAACGCGAGAAGAUGCGCGCCAAGCAGAACCCCCCGGGCCCGGCCCCCCCGGGAGGGGGCAGCAGCGACGCCGCUGGGAAGCCCCCCGCGGGGGCUCUGGGCACCCCGGCGGCCGCCGCUGCCAACGAGCUCAACAACAACCUCCCGGGCGGCGCGCCGGCCGCACCUGCCGUCCCCGGUCCCGGGGGCGUGAACUGCGCGGUCGGCUCCGCCAUGCUGACGCGGGCGGCCCCCGGCCCGCGGCGGUCGGAGGACGAGCCCCCAGCCGCCUCUGCCUCGGCUGCACCGCCGCCCCAGCGUGACGAGGAGGAGCCGGACGGCGUCCCAGAGAAGGGCAAGAGCUCGGGCCCCAGUGCCAGGAAAGGCAAGGGGCAGAUCGAGAAGAGGAAGCUGCGGGAGAAGCGGCGCUCCACCGGCGUGGUCAACAUCCCUGCCGCAGAGUGCUUAGAUGAGUACGAAGAUGAUGAAGCAGGGCAGAAAGAGCGGAAACGAGAAGAUGCAAUUACACAACAGAACACUAUUCAGAAUGAAGCUGUAAACUUACUAGAUCCAGGCAGUUCCUAUCUGCUACAGGAGCCACCUAGAACAGUUUCAGGCAGAUAUAAAAGCACAACCAGUGUCUCUGAAGAAGAUGUCUCAAGUAGAUAUUCUCGAACAGAUAGAAGUGGGUUCCCUAGAUAUAACAGGGAUGCAAAUGUUUCAGGUACUCUGGUUUCAAGUAGCACACUGGAAAAGAAAAUUGAAGAUCUUGAAAAGGAAGUAGUAAGAGAAAGACAAGAAAACCUAAGACUUGUGAGACUGAUGCAAGAUAAAGAGGAAAUGAUUGGAAAACUCAAAGAAGAAAUUGAUUUAUUAAAUAGAGACCUAGAUGACAUAGAAGAUGAAAAUGAACAGCUAAAGCAGGAAAAUAAAACUCUUUUGAAAGUUGUGGGUCAGCUGACCAGGUAGAGGAUUCAAGACUCAAUGUGGAAAAAAUAUUUUAAACUACUGAUUGAAUGUUAAUGGUCAAUGCUAGCACAAUAUUCCUAUGCUGCAAUACAUUAAAAUAACUAAGCAAGUAUAUUUAUUUCUAGCAAACAGAUGUUUGUUUUCAAAAUACUUCUUUUUCAUUAUUGGUUUUAAAAAAGCAUUAUCCUUUUAUCUCACAAAUAAGUAAUAUCUUUCAGUUAUUAAAUGAUAGAUAAUGCCUUUUUGGUUUUGUGUGGUAUUCAACUAAUACAUGGUUUAAAGUCACAGCCGUUUGAAUAUAUUUUAUCUUGGUAGUACAUUUUCUCCCUUAGGAAUAUACAUAGUCUUUGUUUACAUGAGUUCAAAUACUUUUGGGAUGUUACCUUCACAUGUCCUAUUACUGAUGUGUGCAACCUUUUAUGUGUUGAUGACUCACUCAUAAAGGUUUUUGUCUACUGUCAUUUGUUCUUUCCACUUAUUCUAAGCAUUUAGAGUAAUAGAGUCAUACUUUUUUAUAACAGCAACCUUUUAAAAGGAAAGCUCUUAUAAAGUCACUGUCAUGUUUUAGUUGACUAAAUAUAAAUUUAAGAGAAUACUUGAAUUGUGCUAUAGUAAAUAAAAAUUUACUAUUUUGUGUUUGAAUAUUGAAAAAUUGAAUCACUUUAACUCCUGAAAAACAUACAAUUGUAAUUUCAAUGUAAAAUUUCUUAUGUAGGUACUACCUUUUUUUAUCGUUCCAAGGUUUGCUAGUGAACACAGGAUAUUUUAAAAGUUUUUUAUUCUUCGGGCCUGGAAAGUGUACAAAGUCAGUGUAGGAGAAAAAAAUCCAUAUUUUUAUAUUAGCAUGCACACUAAAAACCAAAAUAUUAUUCAUACUUAAAACAUUCAUACAAAACAAUAUGUAAGCAGAAAUAGUACUAAAAUACUUUGCCUAAUUUCUAAGUUGAAGAAUAACACUGGGACACAGUUUUUUCAUAUGAGAGAAUAUUCCGCUAUUUCAAAUUUAAGGGAUUUUCUUCCUAACAUUGAAAUUUUAAAAACAGAGUUACUUCUAAAUAAUUAUACAGAUUUUUUCUUCUAUUAAAUAUUAUUAUUUAGAAUUGUUUUUGUAUUACAUAUUCAUGUUAAGAACCCCGUCUUCCCUUAAAAUACAUUAAAAUUAUGACAUUUUUGCUUUGUGAUUGAAUUUCAAAUAGCAGUAUGGUAUCCUUUUAUCUAGUUAAUAUAUGAAAGUGGCUUGAAUAUAGUCAAAUCCAUUUUAGGUACUCUACUGACUUUUUCCUUCACUUGCCAAGCCCUUUUAUUGUUCACUGUUAGAAAAAUAGAGAAGGUGAGACAGCUGGGGGAAAAUGUGGAGUAAAUGAUAAUCAAAUGUUGAAUUCUAAAAGUCUCUACAUUUACCUAGGUUGGCUUUCUCCCCCAGUUCAGAAGUUUCCAGCUUGGCCAAUCAUCAGAAUCACUUGAGGAACUUAGAAAGAACUCCCUGGCUGUAGCUCCUAUGUAGGUUUAGGUUGAGACUCUGGAUUCCACAAUUUUUAAAGGUUACCAUCUGAGGUUUCUGAUCAUAGUCUACUUUUGAAGCAGCUGCUGCUGUUUCUUUAUUCCAUUGAACACCCUGGAAUUGACAUAAUUUUAUCUAUCAGCAUUUCUCCCCUUUUAGUUUAUUUAAUAAUUAACCCGGUCUCCAGGGCAGUUUUCAUAUGACCAUGUGUAUAUUCACUGCUCACGAAAAAGUUUAAUGUUAGAUUACCAAAUUUAAUAUAGUUACAGAAUUACUGCAUAAGGGCUUCCCUUCUUGGAGACUCUUACCCAGCAUGGGAACAGUGAUCUGCCCACAUGACAGGGUGGUAUGCCAGGCAUAGUUAACUGCUUUUGGUUGUGAGGUACUCAUCUUCCUUUAGUUACCCUUAGUUAUGUGGCACACAUGUCCUUAUUGCCUAGUUCGUCAUCCACACUUUGGAUCUUGUGAAAAUGCUGUUAGUAUCCAACCUUAAAAUAUAUUAGUAUAUGGGUUUUUAUUAAAAGAAUUACUUUGAAUUUUCUAUUUAAUUCAUAUGUAAAUAAAGGAACAUUUCAUUUCACUUAAAAAAAUUAUAUCAGUUAUUAGGCUGGGUGCAGUGGCUCAUGCCUGUAAUCCCAGCACUUUGGGAGGCCAAGGCGGGUGGAUUACCAGAGUUCGGGAGUUUGAGACCAGCUUGACCAACAUGGAGAAACCCCGUCUCUACUAAAAAUACAAAAUUAGCCAGGUGUGGUGGCGCAUGCCUGUAAUCCUGGCUACUCAGGAGGCUGAGGCAGGAGAAUCGCUUGAAAACCCAGGAGACAGAGGUUGCGGUGAGCUGAGAUUGCGCCAUUGUACUCCAGCCUGGGCAAGAAGAGCGAAACUCUGUCUCCAAAAAAAAAAAAAAAAAAAUUAUUAAUACUUUUAAAGACUGAGCUGUUUAAGAAUUUUUUGGGGAACAUUUCUAGCAGUGAUUUUUUUGGCCUUUAAUGAUAGCGUAAAGACAGGAGCCUUACAACUUAGGCAAAGCAUUUCACAUGCAGUCCUUCUUCCAUCUCAAAAUAUGUACUUAUUUUACAUACAGAAUUUUACACUAACCAUUGAAAAAUAAAGUAGGAUCUGCUACAGUUUCACCUGAAAAUUUAUAAAAAGUGUUGAGAUUGGUAGAAGGUAGUUUUUAAGUACAUGUGCACUACCCUAAAAGACUUGUCUAUUGUCAAUAAAGUGUUAGUAUUUGUGAAAUUAUUAUUCCUGUUCAGAAAUACUAUUUCUUAAAUCUCCUGGGAAUUUGUGGCAUAAUAAAGCACAUUCAAAGUUCUAAUGUAUUUAUGAGCUCAUUUUCAAAAUAGUAAGUUUGUCAUCUUUAAAAUGAACAUGACUUGCCUCCUUGAUUUCUGAAAUGAAUUAAUUGAAGAUUGCUAUAGUAAUCUUUAUUUCAUCUUUCUAGAGUUGUUGACAAUUUUAUUAUACAACAGUUACCAUUAGAGAAGGAGGGAAGGGCUUUUGGGUGUGUAUUUAUAGGUACUAAGGGAUUUACUAAAUAUAGUAGAUUAGCACUGUCACACUUGUUCAAGUAGUUUCAAACAUAGAAAAUUAAGUAUCAGGUAUGUGGAGCAAUGUAGUUUUUUUUUUUCUUCAGUUUAAAAAAUUUUUAAUUGUGGUAGAAGCAAUGUAUUCUUAAGGUGAAAAACCUACCUCGGUUACAUGUGGUUUGUGUUUUUUGGAUUAAUCUGGAUUUUAUAAUUAGAAAUAAAAAUGUAAGAUUUUGAAUCCACUUAAUUUCUUGAAAAUAGUACAAGUCAGUGUAAUAGAGAAGCAUUCAUAUAUUCAACACUGUAAGACAAAACAGCAGAGACCUUGGAUUUGAUAAUUGAUCUGAUAUCCUGGACAGUAUUCAUAUGUACAGUGAUAGGUAUCUUUCUUUGGAGUUUUUUUUUUGUGCAUAUGUGUAUAGUUUUAUGGGUUCUGAGUUGGUGACCAGUAAGUUGCAUGUAGUGCUGGCACUUACUUAAUAACUAUUCAUGAUAUUGUUAAUAACUUGUUAUAGGAUUGUAUUCCCAAUUACAGUCUCUAAGAUUGUAAUUGAUAUUAUCUGAGAGGUAGUGUGACAACUUUCUUUUGUUGUUACAUUAAGCCGAAAACAUAAUACUAAUAGACAACUAACAGUUUGCUUAUCAGGCACAUCAACUAAGGCACCUCCCCCCAUGCUAAGUUUCUCCUGGAUAUAUGGAAGUUGAUUGUUUCCCAGUUUAAAAACUUGAACUAAUAUCUCCUAAGAAAAUCUGAGUCCAUAUUGUUUUUAUUUUACUUAGCUAGAAUCUCAUAGCAUGUUAAAGUCAUAUCCUUAUCCCCACUAAAAAUAACUAUGUCUAUGUGAGAGGAAUAUAGUAUGUGGGAGCUGUAUUAAAUACUAUUACAGGUGUUACAGAAUCUUUAAAUAAAUGGACAUGGACCAACUUUCCAUCUAGUAGUGUACGAUCUAUAUAGUGCAUGUCAGUAGCACAAAAUGCAGUCUUAGCAUUAGCCUGUCUAAUCUGAAUAGUUUACUCAAAAGUACUUCUUUGUGUUAAGUAUUCAGCCACUGUUUUUAGAUCUAGUUAAUAGGUUCUAUUUAAUUUGCUACAACAUUUACUGAAUGGUGGAGUGAAAAAACUGAUGCAUACUGGGAAAUAUCUACCAUUUUUUAAAGAUAAUGUUAAUUAGGAAAAGAACACUUUUAAGGAAUUUAUAGCAGUGAUGAAAUGAAUUCAGUUAUAUCAGAUACACCAAACUGUUGAUGGUAUUUAAAUGUGACUUCAAGUUAGUAUUUCUGUAUAUAUUAUUGAUUACUGGUUUGUUUUUAGAUAUGUAAGUCUGUUCUAAUCUACAGUUCACAUAUCGACAGUUACUCUGGUAAUAAUAGAAUGUUAGUGAUGAUCACUUGGUGGAUGUUGAUUAAGUGCCUGUGUUUUGUUUCCUCCUCUGGAUACCAAAUAGGUGUAUGCUACUUUUUUGGUGAACUUAUUUCUUGGAAGAUUUGGCUAUGCUAUUCAGGGUUUUUAUUCUUAUGUUUUUCUUCUAAAUUUAAGUAGCAUCCUGCUGCUACCAUAUUAAAGCUAAAAUUUAACUUUUGCUGAAGAAUCAGCUAAUUCAGGUAAUCCAAAUAUUUGUGGAAAAACAUCUGGAUAAUUUAUUGAACACAUUAGUAUUGUGUUAGACAGCUUUGAUCAUUCCCAUUUCAUAGGUUUUUAUUGUGGAAUAGUCAACUUAAUAUAGAUUCACUUUCAAUUUGCAUGUAUAAAGUAAUACUCAAUAAAAUUUUUUUCAUUUAUUUUUCAACAGUGGUUAUUUUUUUUCUUCCUGUACUAUCAGUAAAAUCCUGACUAUGAGUUUUACUUUUGAAGCUAAAGGAUAAUGCUGGUAAUCUAAUUAUGUACCUCUUACAGAAACCAUAUGCAGCACUUUAAAAAUCUUUAUUUGGUAUAUUAUUUUAGGUGGACAAUGAUUUAAGACUCAAAGCCAUCAUAUUAAGGUCUAAAUACAUUAGUGGUGGGGUUUCUCGAAUAAAUGAGGAAGUGCACAAAAGUUCAGCCUGACUGAAAAUUUUAAUUGUGUUUUAAAACUACAUGAAUAAUUUCUUGAUUCAAAAUCAGAACUCUUAUAAACUAAAUCUGAUGGUGUCCAAAGAAUUUCAGGUCCUUCAAAGUUUGUAAAAGAUAAGUAGGGGCCUAGGAAUAUAAAAAUUUAGACUUUUUUAGUAAAUGGUUUACAUAACCUUUUGUCUUAAUUUGUCAUUCUUCAUACACAGGCACAAGCUAAUCAGUCUUCUCUACUUCUAGAACUCUAAAUCUUCUCAGUAAUGUCAUACAAGUCUAACAAGAGGAAAAGCAUCCUUAAGUCAGUCUAUUUAGAUAAACUCUUCAAGUCCCUAUAUAAGGACGUAUUCCACUAGCAAGCCAGUAAAUUUUUCCAAGGUCACAUAAUCUUACAUGAAAUGGAACCUUUCAUCUUAGACUUCAUCAAACUCAAUUUUUUCCCUUCUAGAUUCACUUUGUGUUUAUGCAUGCAUGCACGCGUGCACACAAUUCUAUCAGCAGCUGUAAACUACCCACAUAUUUUCUUAAUCUCAUUUUUUCAGUUUUUCUUCAUCUUUAAAAGAGGUUACAUUUCAUUCCUGGUCAACUCUUAAAAAGAAUUAUGUAAUGUUGGGCCUUCAUAUUAAAGAGAGAGACUGGUUAUAAGAUCCUUUACAGUCCAUUCAUUUUAUUCUGAUGUCUAACCAGAUAGACACUAGCAAGCAAAACUUCCCUCUUAAUCCUGGACCAAAUGCAUAAUUUUACUGUCACUUUCAAAAAUCUGUUAUGACUGAAUCAAAAUCCUUUUAAAGAAAGGAAAAAGCUCCUUUUGUGUCAAAUAGUUGAACAACAUGAAAACAGUAUGAGCCGGUUAAAGAUAGAUUGAAUUUUUACUUUACACAUAUGAAAAACAGUAAGUUUUGACUGCUGUGUAUGUUAUUCAUGUUAAUAUGUGCUCAGUUAUUCACUAUUGUUAAUCCACAUAUAAUCAGUUGCUAUCCCUGGUUAGACACACUAUGGAACUUGAAAUGCACAAUAUUUACAUUGUUAGAGGCUUCUAUCCAAAUAUCUGCAUUCCUUUAAAAUGUGAACUAUUUGCUGUGAUUAACCAAAGGUAGAUUAUGUCAUCAGUGGACAUUUUAGCUUUAUGGAAACAAAUUAUUAAGAAAUGAAUAGAAAGGUGUCUUUUUCUUUGUGUAGUGCAAAAGCCUAAAGCUAUCAGUCAAAGGCCUAAGAAAUCCACAUUUGAAAAACGUAAAUCAUGAUUGGUAAGAAUACAUUCAUCUGAUAGUAUUGAGAAAAGUUGAAAAACUGUUAGCCUUCCAUAACACAUUAAACAUUUUAUGUAUGGAUGGCUGAAAGUAUUGAGAAAAGCUGAAAAACUGUUAGCCUUCCAUAACACAUUAAACGUUUUGUGUAUGGAUGGCUUAGGACAAUAAACAACAUCAUUAAAGUAAAAUUAUGUCAGUCUGUUCAUAUUAACUUAUUUAAAUCAAUGAAAAUUUUGAUGAGAUGACUAAAUGGAUGCUUUGGAAAUGCAGGAUUAUAGGAGGCCUAAAAGUGCAUCUUGUUUCUUGUAACCCUUUUAAAACCAAUAUGCCUGGCUAGGUGCAGUGGCUCAUGCCUGUAAUACCAACGGGGUAACACAGGGUUAUGCCGUCUAUACAAAAAAAUAAAUGAGCUGGGCAAGAUGGCAUGCACCUGUAGUCCCAGCUGCUUGGUAGGCUGAGGGGGAAGGAUUGCUUGAGCCUGGGAGGUCGAGACUGCAGUGAGCCAAGAUCACACCACUGCACUCCAGCCUGGGUGACAGAGCAAGACUCUACCUCAAAAAUAAAAAUAAUCAAUAUAGUUUCAAUGAAGCAAAGCAUCUCAGGUAACAAUUUGAGCAUAACUUUAACCAUAACUUAUGAUAGCAUAAUAACAUUCAUUAGUAAUUCAGUAGCCGUAUGUGCCAGGCUGUGUUAGGUGCUUUAUAUAUUGUUUAAUUUUUAAAAACUUGUGGAGUGUACAGAUUGGUAAGGUGACAUUGUAUCACAAAGCUAGUCUUUGAGUCCAAAGUUUUGUGGUUUUAUGUUAUGAUAUACUUUUAUCAUGGAAUUGUCUUAUUAAAUGUUUUGCCAGUGGUUCUUAAAGUGUGUUUCUGACACCAGUAGCAUUGACUUCACUUAGAAACCUGUUAGAAAUACAAAUUAUUUGGCCCCACCCAACACUUGAGUCACAAACUUUGCAGAUGGGGCUCAAUCUGUUUUAACAAGCGCUUCAUGUAAUUUUGAUGCAGGCCUAAGUUUUUGAGCCACUGCAGUAUGCAUUUCUAUUUUUAAGCAAAGAUCUUGGUCUUUCUUUUUGGACAUUGUAGAAAUAACAUGAACUUGUUUUUUGUUUGUUUUUGUUUUGUUUUGUUUUAAGCUCCUGAUCUUUGUUGGUUAUGUUGCAAAAGAUUGUAUCAGGAGAAGCCUCAGCAUGGACAUUGGCAUCCUGACAUAACCCCCAUUAAUUUAGUAUUCUUUCUGAAACUCAAAUGGAUUCUCAAGUCCAAGAGACUAUGGAAUAAAAUCAUUGUUUGUCUGUGUUAAGUUUUAUCUCUGUUAUUGCCUGAAGACUUUUGGUAACAAUAAUGCGCUUUCAUCAAACUUUUAAGACUUGAUUGGAAAAAAUAAAUGUAUGUUUCAUCAGUUA